UUUUUAUUCUUUCUGCCAGGUACAUCAGAUCCAUCAGGUCCAAGCUGUGUUGACUACCACUACUUUUCCCUUCGUCUCAAUUAUGUCUUGGAAGAAGGCUUUGCGGAUCCCUGGAGGCCUUCGGGUAGCAACUGUGACCUUGAUGCUGGCGAUGCUGAGCACCCCGGUGGCUGAGGGCAGAGACUCUCCCGAGGAUUUCGUGUACCAGUUUAAGGGCAUGUGCUACUUCACCAACGGGACCGAGCGCGUGCGGGGUGUGACCAGAUACAUCUAUAACCGAGAGGAGUACGCGCGCUUCGACAGCGACGUGGGGGUGUAUCGGGCGGUGACGCCGCUGGGGCCGCCUGCCGCCGAGUACUGGAACAGCCAGAAGGAAGUCCUGGAGAGGACCCGGGCGGAGUUGGACACGGUGUGCAGACACAACUACCAGUUGGAGCUCCGCACGACCUUGCAGCGGCGAGUGGAGCCCACAGUGACCAUCUCCCCAUCCAGGACAGAGGCCCUCAACCACCACAACCUGCUGGUCUGCUCAGUGACAGAUUUCUAUCCAGCCCAGAUCAAAGUCCGGUGGUUUCGGAAUGACCAGGAGGAGACAACUGGCGUUGUGUCCACCCCCCUUAUUAGGAACGGUGACUGGACCUUCCAGAUCCUGGUGAUGCUGGAAAUGACUCCCCAGCGUGGAGACGUCUACACCUGCCACGUGGAGCACCCCAGCCUCCAGAACCCCAUCAUCGUGGAGUGGCGGGCUCAGUCUGAAUCUGCCCAGAGCAAGAUGCUGAGUGGCAUUGGAGGCUUCGUGCUGGGGCUGAUCUUCCUCGGGCUGGGCCUUAUUAUCCAUCACAGGAGUCAGAAAGGGCUCCUGCACUGACUCCUGAGACUAUUUUAACUGGGAUUGGUUAUCACUUUUCUGUAACGCCUGCUUGUCCCUGCCCAGAAUUCCCAGCUGCCUGUGUCAGCCUGUCCCCCUGAGAUCAGAGUCCUACAGUGGCUGUCACGCAGCCACCAGGUCAUCUCCUUUCAUCCCCACCUCGAGGCUGAUGGCUGUGACCCUGCUUCCUGCACUUACCCAGAGCCUCUGCCUGUGCACGGCCAGCUGCGUCUACUGAGGCCCCAAGGGGUUUCUGUUUCUAUUCUCUCCUCAGACUGCUCAAGAGAAGCACAUGAAAACCAUUACCUGACUUUAGAGCUUUUUUACAUAAUUAAACAUGAUCCUGAGUUAUCUGUAUUCUCAACUUCCUUAAUUGAGCAGAGGCAGGAAAUCACUGCAGAAUGAAGGAACAUACCUUGAGGUGACCCAGCCAACCUGUGCCCAGAAGGAGGGUUGUACCUUGAAAAGACACUGAAAGAAUUUGGGGUGCAAAGUCAGGGUGGGCAGAGGAGGUAGAAGAUCAACUCAGUUGUUGCAUCAUUCAUGGUUCUUUCAUAUUGAUGCUCAGUGCAGUGGCCUGAGAAUAUCCCAGCCUCUCUUCUGGUUUGGUGAGUGCUAUAUAAGUAAGCAUGGUGGAAUUGUUUGGGGGCAGAUAUAGUGACCCUUGGUCACUGGUGUUUCAAACAUUCUGGCAAGUCACAUCAAUCAAGAAUAAUUUUUACUUUUAAGAAAGCAUAACCAGCAAUAAAAGUACUAUUUUUGAUUCUAAAUGA